AGAUUGGGGCCUGUGGAGGCCGCACUAGGAUCGUAGAAGGAGUGGAGCCGUGCUCUCACCCUGUCUUAGAGGACCCGGAAGCGCCAAGUGACUGAGGGCCGAAGACACUCACCUGUGGAGCCUGUGCACGUAGGUAGAGGCGGCGGCUCUGAGUCCAGGAGCUCCAGUGGGCAGCUCCCCAGCGGCUGCAGGCCCCCUGGACACCCAGAACGUAGAGUCUGGAGAGGAGACGUCGAAACCUCCCAGGGGAGGCUGGCCCAGCUUUACCCCAGCCUGACUGUGUGACCUUGAGGAGGACAGCCACUUUCUCUGCACCAGCCAUGAACUACGUGGGGCAGCUGGCGGAGACGGUGUUUGGGACGGUGAAGGAGCUGUACCGGGGCCUGAACCCAGCCACACUGAGCGGCGGCAUUGACGUGCUGGUGGUGAAGCAGGUGGACGGCUCGUUCCGGUGCUCACCCUUCCACGUGCGUUUUGGCAAGCUGGGCGUCCUGCGGUCGCGGGAGAAGGUGGUAGACAUUGAGCUCAAUGGGGAGCCUGUGGACUUGCACAUGAAGCUUGGGGACAGCGGGGAGGCCUUCUUUGUUCAGGAGCUGGAGAGCGAUGAUGAACAUGUGCCUCCCGGCCUGUGCACCUCACCCAUCCCUUGGGGGGGUCUGUCUGGCUUCCCCUCGGACUCCCAGCUGGGCACUGCCAGUGAGCCUGAGGGCCUCGUCAUGGCAGGCACGGCCUCCACUGGGCGGAGGAAGAGGCGUCGCAGGAGGAAACCCAAGCAGAAAGAGGAUGCAGUGGCAACUGAUUCUAGUCCAGAGGAACUGGAGGCAGGCGCUGAGAGUGAGCUAUCCCUGCCGGAAAAGCUGAGGCCAGAGCCCCCAGGCAGUGUCCAGUUGGAAGAGAAGUCUUCACUGCAGCCCAAAGACAUCUACCCCUACUCGGAUGGCGAGUGGCCCCCCCAGGCCAGCCUCUCAGCAGGUGAGCUAACAUCCCCUAAGAGCGACUCGGAGCUGGAGGUGCGGACCCCGGAGCCCAGUCCCCUAAGAGCCGAGUCCCACAUGCAGUGGGCCUGGGGGAGGCUGCCUAAGGUGGCCAGAGCUGAGCGGCCCGAGUCCUCAGUGGUCCUUGAAGGCAGAGCUGGGGCAACCUCUCCUCCUCGGGGAGGACCCAGCACUCCCUCUACCUCUGUGGCUGGCGGCGUGGACCCUUUGGGACUCCCAAUCCAGCAAACAGAGGCUGGUGCCGACCUUCAGCCUGACACAGAGGAUCCCACUCUAGUGGGUCCCCCUCUCCACACCCCAGAGACAGAGGAAAGCAAGACUCAGAGCUCUGGGGACAUGGGCCUCCCUCCUGCCUCCAAGUCAUGGAGCUGGGCCACUCUGGAGGUUCCAGUUCCCACCGGGCAGCCAGAGAGGGUCUCCAGGGGGAAAGGCUCCCCAAAGAGAAGCCAGCACCUGGGCCCCAGUGACAUCUACCUGGAUGACUUGCCCUCCCUGGACUCUGAGAAUGCAGCGCUUUACUUCCCCCAAAGUGACUCUGGGCUGGGGGCCAGAAGAUGGAGUGAACCCAGCAGUCAGAAGUCCCUGAGGGACCCCAACCCUGAACAUGAACCUGAACCCACUCUGGACACAGUGGAUACAAUAGCACUGUCCCUCUGUGGUGGACUGGCUGACAGCCGGGACAUCUCCCUAGAGAAAUUCAACCAGCACAGCGUCUCUUACCAGGACCUCACCAAAAACCCCGGACUUUUGGAUGACCCAAACCUAGUGGUGAAAAUCAAUGGAAAGCAUUAUAACUGGGCUGUGGCUGCCCCCAUGAUCCUCUCCCUGCAAGCCUUCCAGAAAAACUUGCCCAAGAGCACCAUGGACAAGCUGGAGAGGGAGAAGAUGCCCCGGAAGGGUGGGCGAUGGUGGUUUUCCUGGCGACGCAGGGACUUCCUGGCCGAGGAGCGCAGUGCCCAGAAGGAGAAGACUGCAGCCAAGGAGCAGCAGGGGGAGAAGACAGAAGUCCUGAGCAGUGAUGACGAUGCCCCAGACAGCCCUGUGAUCCUGGAGAUCCCCUCCUUGCCACCCUCCACUCCACCCUCCACUCCUACCUACAAGAAGUCCCUCCGCCUCUCCUCCGAUCAGAUCCGGCGCCUGAACCUGCAAGAAGGUGCCAAUGAUGUGGUCUUCAGCGUGACCACUCAGUACCAGGGCACCUGCCGCUGCAAGGCCACCAUCUACCUGUGGAAAUGGGACGACAAGGUGGUCAUCUCUGACAUCGACGGCACCAUCACCAAGUCAGAUGCUCUGGGCCAUAUCCUGCCCCAGCUGGGGAAAGACUGGACACACCAGGGCAUCACCAGUCUCUAUCACAAAAUCCAACUGAUCAGGGCCCACCUACUGGCCUGCAGCCGGAGGGGAGGCCCUCUCCAUCCUGGUCCACCCAGGCCUCAGGACUCUGUGCACCGUCCAGCUGAGUCCACUGCCUGGCCGUUCUCUUCAAGUCCCCUCCCUGCAAAGGUUGGAACAUCAGAGUCCCACAGUUGGGCUGGGCAGGCUAAAGCCAGAGAAACAGAUGGGGGCUGGCUGGUCUCUGAUGGCUCUAUGCCACCCUGUCCCCCACUCUCAGAAAUGGGUACAAGUUCCUGUACUGCUCGGCGCGGGCCAUUGGCAUGGCGGACCUCACCAAGGGGUACCUGCAGUGGAGAGGUGAUCGAGAAGAAACCAGAGGUGUUCAAGGUCGCCUGCCUGAGUGACAUCCAGCAGCUGUUUCUGCCCCACGGACAGCCCUUCUAUGCUGCCUUUGGGAAUAGGCCCAAUGAUGUCUUUGCCUACCGGCAGGUGGGCCUGCCUGAGUCACGCAUCUUCACAGUCAACCCCCGGGGAGAGCUCAUCCAGGAGCUCAUAAAGAACCACAAAUCCACGUAUGAGCGGCUUGGUGAAGUGGUCGAGCUCCUCUUCCCACCUGUGGCCCGUGGCCCCAGCACAGACCUGGCCAACCCUGAAUACAGUAACUUCUGCUACUGGCGGGAGCCACUGCCUGCUGUGGACCUUGAUACCCUGGACUGAACCUGCCCUGGCUGGCUCCUCCUCCCUGGCCCGGCCCAGGACUGGCUAGGUGUCCUGGGGUAUAGGAGGGUGGGAAUUGGAGUGUCAUGGGGCAAACCCACUGAAGGGGAAGGAGGAGGCUGCAGGUUGGUUGGCAGCUAGAGAGACUCCCCCAUCUUCCCCGUCAUAUUUUUGCCAGCUAAGCUGCAGCUGCUCCAGGCGUCAGUGUGGCACUGUCCUGGGGCAAUUAGCUUGUCAUCUGGGCCCUUGCAGGGUUCUUUUUUUUUUUUUUUUUUUUUUUUUCCUGAGACAGGGUCUUGUUCUGUUGCCCAGGCUGGAGUGCAGUGGCAUGAUCUCUCGGCUCACUGCAACCUCCGCCUCCCGGGUUCAAGCGAUUCACCUGCCUCAGCCUCCCAAGUAGCUGGGAUUACAGGCGUGUACCACCACGCCUGGCUAAUUUUCGUGUUUUUAGUAGAGAUGGGUUUUCACCACAUUGGCCAGGCUGGUCUCGAACUCCUGACCUCAAGUGAUUUGCCCACCUCGGCCUCCCAAAGUGCUGGGAUUACAGGCAUGAGCUACCAUGCCAGGCCUCCUUGCAGGGUUUUCUAUGCCCUUGAUAUCUGUCUCCCUGUCAACCUGGGACCUUGCUGUAAGUCUUGAUAGGACAGGGAGAAGAGGGAGGCCCUACCGAGGCUCGAGGCUUCAGUGAAGGGUGACAGCAGUGGGAGUGUGGUACAGCCUCUGGAAGGACACAGUGUUCUCCCCGCCCCUUGUCUGGGAGCCAGGACUGUACCCUCCGAAGCCAGACAUCACUGCCAACAUAUCCCCCUUGCUGGUGCCCUGGCAUCUCAGCACAUGACACACACCCACACCUGCAGGCUGUGGUUCCGGCUUGGCCUGCUCCCCGUCCGGCUGCUGCCGCUGCCUCUCUCCAGACCUCGCUUAAGGACAGUCCCAAACUCAGCUGGGGCAGGUGUUGGCCUGAAAGUCCUCCCCCAGCCUCUGCUGGCCAGCUUGGUGCUCACAGCUGCUGGGUAAGCUCUUGCCUAAGGAGCUGUGGGAAGCAGGGCUGAUGCCCCAGCAACCUCUCCUCCCACUGUCUUUGAAGAAAGUAGCUUUAGACCGGCUAAAAGCUUUAAUCCAGAGCCUGCCCUACUCUGAUAGUACCAGAGUGGAGGGCAGAAUACCAAAUGUCCAGGAACCAAAGGCAGGGCUGUGGGGACCUGAAGAGCAGCACAGUGGGGCCCGUGCUGCUGUGGGGGAAACUGAGGCUGGGAGCCUCAGCAGAGACCGGUGUCAAGAGUCUCUGGGAACUGCAUAGGCCUGAGGAACAUGCAUUUUCAAGUUGUCCAUUGAUGGUUUCGUACCUGAAUUUCUCACCUUUUGUGAACAUCUUGGGAGGGUGGGGGUUUUGCAGGGGUGUUAAAAGCAAGGCUUGGAGCCCCUUUCCUCCAGCUGGUGGCUCCUUCUCAGGGCCUGGCCUCAUUCAGGCCACUUUGUAGAGAAAUGCCCUGACCUCGCAGGAAGGAUUUCCCCACCCCCAAGUGGAAGGAAGAGGACAGUGUGGGCACCAGAGGGCCCUGGAAACAUCUUAGGGGAAGGAAAGGAAAAGGAUAAAUUUGGAGUGGGGGGUCUCUAAACAGAUUGCCUGGAUUCCGUUCUUUCCUGGGGUUCUACAGCUGCCUAAGCCCUCACCUUGGGGGAGGAUCAAAGGGAAUAAAGAGAACUCUUGGCUGA